AGCUGCCGACGUGGGGCGGGCAGCCGCCGGCGGCUGGGAGCCGAGGCGUCGGUGCAGACCUGGAGACGGGCAUGGGGGGGCUGCGGCUGCUGGCUGUGGCCCUCACGUGCUGCUGGUGGCCGCAGGGCAGCCAGGGUAAGACCCUGCGGGGCAGCUUCAGCAGCACCGCGGCCCAGGACGCCCAGGGCCAGCGCAUCGGCCACUUCGAGUUCCAUGGUGACCAUGCUCUUCUGUGUGUCAGAAUCAACAACAUAGCAGUAGCUGUUGGAAAAGAAGCUAAACUCUACCUGUUCCAAGCCCAGGAAUGGCUAAAGCUACAGCAAAGCAGUCAUGGUUAUAGCUGUAGUGAAAAAUUAUCCAAAGCUCAGUUGACAAUGACCAUGAACCAGACCGAACAUAAUCUGACAGUGUCCCAGAUUCCGUCUCCACAAACGUGGCAUGUGUUUUAUGCAGACAAGUAUACAUGCCAAGAUGACAAGGAGAAUUCUCAGGUGGAAGAUAUCCCAUUUGAAAUGGUGUUACUAAACCCAGAUGCCGAAGGGAAUCCAUUUGAUCAUUUUAGUGCUGGAGAAUCUGGGUUACAUGAGUUCUUUUUCCUCCUAGUCCUAGUGUACUUUGUGAUUGCUUGCAUUUAUGCUCAAUCAUUGUGGCAGGCUAUUAAGAAAGGCGGACCCAUGCACAUGAUUUUAAAGGUUCUGACAACUGCAUUGCUGUUACAAGCUGGUUCAGCUUUAGCUAAUUACAUUCAUUUCUCCAGUUACUCCAAAGAUGGAAUAGGGGUACCAUUUAUGGGAAGUUUGGCAGAAUUUUUUGACAUCGCUUCCCAAAUUCAGAUGUUAUACUUACUUUUGAGUCUAUGCAUGGGUUGGACAAUAGUCAGAAUGAAGAAGUCUCAAAGCAGACCUCUCCAGUGGGAUUCUACGCCUGCAUCCACUGGCAUUGCAGUAUUCAUUGUCAUGACACAGAGUGUUUUGCUACUUUGGGAACAGUUUGAAGAUAUCAGUCAUCAUAGCUACCAUUCACACCACAACUUAGCAGGGAUCCUCCUAAUUGUUCUAAGAAUUUGCCUAGCAUUGUCAUUAGGCUGUGGACUCUAUCAGAUCAUCACAGUGGAGAGAAGUACACUCAAAAGGGAGUUCUACAUCACAUUUGCCAAAGGCUGUAUCUUGUGGUUUUUAUGCCAUCCAGUUCUUGCAUGCAUUUCUGUCAUUUUUAGCGACUACCAAAGAGACAAGGUUAUUACAAUAGGUGUUAUCCUUUGCCAGUCUGUUUCCAUGGUUAUUCUCUACAGACUCUUUCUGUCUCACAGUCUAUACUGGGAAGUUUCUUCACUUUCUUCAGUAACACUACCACUGACCAUAUCAUCUGGACACAAAAGUCGCCCUCAUUUCUGAUACUUGAUUUUUGUUGAGAGGAAAAGUGAAUUGGUUAAAAGAGUGCAAUAAGGAUCCAAAUACAGUGACUUUUUUUUCAUACAUUUAGUAUGAAAACUUGAACAGCGAAAGCAGAGCAUGUUAUUUAUAUAACUGCAUUUAAGCAGUACCAAGACUGAAAAAAAAGGUAAUAAAUGAAAUGUUUUGAAAUAUACUUAAACAACAAACUUUGAAGAAAGUGUUGUUAUAAAAUUAUUGAAGCGAUUUCUAUGUGGAAAUAAAUGUGAAAAAUAACUAUGAUAUUUUGGUAAAAUAUUCACCACUUAUAAUGCCUCAUCUUAAUAGCUAACUCAGGUUUAAUAGUCUUAUAAAAAGUAAUCAGUUAAAUGAUUACUUGCUUAUAAAUAUCUAAACUAGUCCAGUUAUGAAAUCAGUGUAAUACAUUGAUUUUUAAAACUGCUGCUUUUUAUGCUUUAAGGAAAAUGUAUUUCAUAUUUGAGUUUAAAGGAAUUGAAAUUACUUCAGGAAAUGAAUAUAAAAUAGGUUCACAGUUAAAUGAAUAAGCUUUUGUUUAUUUGUGGGUGGAGUUAUUCUCCAAUUUUUUCUGCCAUUUUUGGCUCUAGUUCAGGUUUUAGCUUGAUUAGCAAAGGUUUUUGACAAACAGUUUAUGAAAAAAUAAAACUUAAAUACAUUACACGGGUUGUAAGGACAAAGGAUUUUAAAAUCUGAGCACUUAGGUGAAGGGACAAGCAGGUUUAUGUGUUUAAACAGAAAGAAGGGAAAAGGUACUAUGUGAUAUGGUACUGAAAUUUUGAUCCCAAUAGAAUUCAUUUCUCUUACGUUGAAUCCCCAAUCAUAAUUAAGCCGUAUACACAGAUUAAAUUAACAGAAGCAUUUCACAUAAAUGUUGGUUUCAGUCAUCAACUACCCAUGAAUUCCUGCCCAAGGAUACUUAAUCAGGAUUAAAUUUUCUAUGAAUAAUUGAAAAACAAAACACUCACUGGAUUUGUUAUAAUCCGUGUUGGCACUGGAUUCUAAGUAGUUGCCAUCUUGAAUCCUUUGUAAUAAAGCCAUACUUUUGUGUGUGUGUGUGAUGCCCCAGUAUUGAGUAUGCUAGCUAAAAAAUAUCAAGUGCCUGAUUAAAGAAUUGCUAAAUGGUUGUCAAUACUCGCUGUAUAAAAUGAGUAUUCCCAUUAAUAGUCACUGAUUGGAAAUUAUUCUGUUGCUGUUUGUCAAGCUGUUCAGGCCUUUUCCUUUUUACUUCUGGCUUAUUUUAAAAAUAUUUUUUAUCUAUUUACUGUGUGUUUAAGCAAGCAACAGUGCACUGAUCUGGUAGUUAAAUUUUUUAAUUAAAUAGUUAAAAUAAUGUAGUGCAACUUAAAAAUAUCUAUGGCUUUGUUUUUGUUUUUCUUUUGUACCUAGUCUCAUUGGAAAUGACUAGUAUUCUGCCUCAUUUUCAGGGCAGAAUAUGUGUUUGUGACCCAAAAUGACAAAGUUACCAAGUUCAACCUGCUCAUUAAAUCAUCUCUCUAUUAGUUCUUUGUAAAUCACUUAGUACAUUAGAGCUACAGGUUAAGACUAGAAAGUCUGAGUUAUGUUUUAGGUAUACAUGAUCGUCUGAGUGGUCAUAACCUUUUCUUUUAUCAUGUCUCGCUAAUAACCCCAGCUAUUGUCUGUUGUGUUCAGCUGAGAUGCAAAAAAGAAAUUAAGCAAAAAAGAAAAAGAUGAAGACUUUUCAUGAAUUUUGUGAACUUGCCAAAAGGGGAAGGGAAAAAUCUUUGUGUUACUUCACUCAAAGAACAUAAGUAACUGCAAUUAACAUAUAUGAAAUUUAUUACUCUGCUUGCAUUUAUGAAACUAACCAGUUUUUUAAACUUUAAUUCUUAAAUUUAUGGUUGGAAAUGCUGAUAAUUUAUUUUGUUAUUUAAGAGCUGUUGUUAAGUGGAGGAAAGUAGUUGUUAAUAAAUGUAUAAAACUGUUCUUGACUAGUAAUCAGGGACAAAAUUUAUAGUUCAUAAGUCAUGACACAGUAUUCGCUCUUUUUCUGAAUGUUUACAUAGAGAUUCAUCACUGCAGAUUACAGAAAGUUAAGUGUAUACUACAAACUCUAAUUAAAGAUAAAAAUCUUUUCUACUUUUCUUUGUCAGAUAAUGCUUUUUUAUGUGUUUUUACAUUUUUUGAAAGAAGAUAAAUGGUUCAUCCAGAGCUUUAUUAAGAAGCAUUUCUUUUCUUCCCUUAAAAAAUAGAUGCUUAUUUUUAUUGACAUGUGUAUAAUAAGAUGGGUGCCUACUGUGAUGCAUUUUACCAGGCAUUUUACCUUCAUUAUUACUCAUCUCUAUUGUGAUAACCAGGCUCCCAUUUAACUGAGUAUAAGAGAGAAUAAAUGAUUUCUCUAAGGUCAUCAAACUAUUUAGUUUUUCCACUUUACCUUCAUGAUUUAAGGAACAUGUAUUAGCUGUGUUUUAGUGAGAAUGAAUUGCUAUCCAUCAUAAUUUUUGCUGUUGAUUUGAACAUUAAAACUGGAAUUGUGCUAAAAUCAGAACAUGCGCUUGAAUAUCUGUAAGACCUCAGCACACUUCAGUAUUUGAACCUGGCUUUUAACCAGACAGUAUUACUAGCAGGAGAGUUAAUCUAGGCAGAAGAGCUUGCUUUAGGGUAAUUAUUUAUUAUCUCCAGUAAAGUCACAUCUGAUGAACAUAGGAGAUACACAAAUCUGAGAUCAUCUCUAAAAUAAUGAGACUAGAACCUAUCUAUCAACAUGAACAUGGGCUCCUUCAGCAUGUUUCUUCUAGGAGACUGCACGUUCUUUGGAAUUUGGAAAUUUGGAAUUAUCUGUGAAACAUUUUCUUAAAUAGCUUCUGUGGUAUCAAAUCAUUGAGGUUGUUUUUUGUUUGUUUUGAGAAUUGAUAUGAUUGUUAGAAGUAGCCAGAUACGAAGAGGUAAUACUGUUUUUUAUUCCAACAUGUAUUUGUGAAUUGAGACUAAAAUAAUGAGAUUGGUUUUCCUCUGUGAUCUGAAAGUAGUGUGGUAGAAGCACCGUAGCUUGAUUUCUUGCAAUAGCUCUCUAAGUAAUAUUACCAUGUCCACACUUGGGCAGCCUUCUGCACAGCUCCAGGGGCAUCAUAUGUGUUGUGCUGUAGGAGUGCCAUGAAGCCUGGAGGUGAGGAAAGAAGUGAUCCUGCCCACUAGGGCCAUUCUCCACAGUGUAGCCAAAACAAUCUCUUAAAAAUGGAAAUCAUCUGGAUGAUGAGCAUACAGAAAUUCUUUGUGCUAAUCUUGUAAUUUUUUUGUAAGUUUGAAAUUAUUUCAAAAAGUUUAAAAAUCAUAUAAAUCAGAUCAAACUACUACUUCCCUGACAAAAACCCUCCAUGUGCCUCUCAUUGCACUUAGGAAAAGAAGUCCUCACUCAUUACUAUGUUCUGCAAGGCCCAUAUGAUCUGGUUAUCUCUUAAUUUGUACCACUCUCUCACACACAUAUCCCAGCCUCAUUGUCCUUCAUCAAAAAAAGAUCUAGCUUAUAUCACACCCUCAGAUACUUGGCACUAGCCAUCUUCUCUGCCUGGGACAUUCUCUUCCAAAUCUUAGCAUGGUUGGAAGGCUGAAUCCUCAUCCUUCAGGUUCUCAGCUGAGAUGUCUUUUAGAGAACUCACCAUCUGUGGUGGAUUUAUAUGGUGCAGUUUAGUCAACCUGGAGAUAGGUUCUGCAGAAUUCUCUUCCAUGCAUAAUUUCAGGACAAUGUAGGCCAUAAGAAAUGUUUGAUACAAGAUAUAGAAGGCAGAAGUAAAGUAGCAGCCAGAUCUGCAUUCUUUUUGUAAGAGGAAGGGCCAGACAAGGCACAAGGCACAAGGCACUGUUGCAGCUUAUCCACAUUAUUGCUUAUCUGUUGGCUUCUCUUGGCCUGUGGGACAACAGCCAGGCCCACAGGAACACCAGUUCCUGCCGGAAUGGCUCCUUCAGCUUCUCUGGCUCCUGGGCCAGGUGUGCGUUUUACUCUGACAAAGGGUGCCAGCUUCUGCUGGACAACUCCAUCAUUCACACUGGAGGAUUAGAGGCAGGGAGAGACCUGUAUGGCUUCCAGUCCAUCCUCACAAGUUCCACUCAGUUCCCACAGGUUCUACUCAUCCUAGCAAGUUCCUUGCUUCCCCCAUUUCCCAUGUCUUCCCUUUCCAACUGCCAGACACAAAAGAAACCGCCUCCUAUAAUCCCUAUAAUAAGCCCCUUAUUUUGAAUAUUAAGAUAUGUGUAUGUGUAUUAGAUCCUAGUGGUUCUUUUCUGAUCAGACCCUGAUUAACCAUACCAUCCUACCUAAUGCUAUUCCCCCAUCCUAGUUCUAUCAUAUUAUCCCUUUUUUUGUUUGUUGUACUUAGCUGGUUUAUCUUUGUCAUCUCUCAAAUUAGAAUAUAAAUUUUAAGUGAGUUUGUCUCUAUUGUUCAUUGCUGUAUGCCUAAUACUAGGACACUCCCUGGUGCAUACUAGAUGCUCAAAAAUAUUUUUGAGUGAAUGAAGGCAAUGCUGAAAAAGUUCCAAAUCUGUACUUAACAGUGUAGUAUUAAUUAUGUAAUAGAAGUACCCGUAGUGACUUCAAUAAUACCUUGCCUAUUCUUUGUUCAAUUGCAUGGAACUUGGUAGUGUGUAAAAAUCUUGACUAGUCAAGUAGUUGUCAUAAAACAUCAGUUACGAGAGGAUUUCUCAAAUUCUCACAGAGGCAGUUUCUCUUUAUUUUAUGUAGUCCUGUAAUAGGACCAUGUGUCUGGUUUCUGGCCUGCCACAACCAGAAGCACCAAUUUAAAAGAGAAGUUUCUAGUCAGCUAGAGGAGGGAAUGUUGACAGUAGUCAGAAGCAGCUGGGAAAAGAUGGGAAAACUAGAAAUGACAAUAACACUCAAAUUGCAGCAGCCUGGGGUCAUUUAGUGUAGGUGAAAGCAGCCCUGUGUUGUGUAUCUCAGUAGACUCUUAAGAGAUUUGUUGUUCAAUGUAUUCAUGACAGUGACUGAUGGUAAUCAAGAAAAUAUUAAGUUAUAAGUUAUGUUCAGUAGCCUCAAAGAAGUAUGCGAAAACCUUCUAAUGUUUUCUUCUUGUUAAACAGGUAAUAUAUGCACAUUGUACAAAAAUCAGAAAGUUGAAAAAGGUGGGGAAAAGAAGUCCUUCUCUCACUCAUUUCCCUUCCCUGAAUCCAAACUCUGUUACCAGUUAUCUUUCUAGAAAUGGCCCCAUGCACAUAUAAACAUAUAUGAAACACAAAUUAUAGCAUAACAUACAGACUUUUGCACAUUCAGCAAUUUAUUCUGUAGCCUUACCUAGAAUUGUCCCAUUUUUUUCACCAAUUGCAUAGAACUCCAUUAUAUGGAUGUAUUUUGAUUUUUUCAAAGAAUCAGUUCUGUUACUGCACGUUGUUGGUUUUCAGUCUUGCUAAUACAGACAAGGCUGAAAUUAAGACAGUAAUCAAGAAUUUGCCAAGACUUCCUUCCCUCCUCCCAAAAUGCCUCCACUCCAGGUUCCAGGUCUAGAUCCUUGGGAUUUUCUAGGUGAUGGAAGUAUCUUUGUUAUUCAUAGUGAGCUCUGAUAGUUACGCUAACCAGAUGACUCAAAUAGGGGCUAGCCACACCAGAAGACCAACCAUUGGAUUAGAGGGUUGGAGUUUUGAGUCAUAUGAUAUUAGCCCAACCUCUGAGGUGGAGAGAGGGGUUAGAGAUGGAGUUCAGCUUUAUAUAGAGAUUGAGUCAAUUAAUCAUGCCUGUCAUGAAACCCCGAGAGAAACUCUGGUCAGUGAUGCUCAAGUGAACUUCCCUGGUUGGCAAUACUCUGGUGUGUUCUAGGAGGGUGACAUGUCCCUGAGGGCACAGAAACUUUGUGUUUGGGAUCCUCUUACACCUUGCUCUAUGUAUGUCUUCUUUUGGCUGUUCUGAUUUGUAUCCUUUUGCUAUAAUAAACUGUAAUAGUACGCAUAGCACUUUGCUGAGUUCUGUGAGUUGUUCUAUUUAAUUAUAGAACCUGAAGGUAUUGUGGGGACCCCUGAACUUGCAGCCAGUUGGUCAGAAGUAAGGAUGGUCCUGGGAAUGCCCAAAGUUGCUAGUUUCUGAAGUGAGGGCAGUCAUAUGGAGGACUGGGCCCUUAAUCUGUGAAGUUUGGCUUAACUUCAGGCAGUUGGUGUCAGAAGCCAUUGCAAAUAUCCUGAUGAUCCGUGCAAAACAAAAACACUUAACAGAAAAUUACGUUGUACUCUCUGUACGGAUAAUUUUCGGUUAAGUGUUUUUGUUUUCCAUGGAUUGUACUAGAUAUCAAUCUGAUAAAUAACUUUUAUUCAUUAUAGUUUUAAUUUGCAUUUCUCUUAUUAAUUUUUGUUUUAAAACCAUUUUCUUUCCAGUUCUACGAUCUGUUAACAUAUUUUUCCCACUUUUCUAUUGGGUUGGUUGUCUUUUUCUUAUUGAUUUGUUAAAACUCUUUAUAACAGAAAUUGGUCAUUUGUGAUAUGAGUCUGAACUGUGUUUCUCAAUUUGUGAUUUUUCUCUUUACUUUUUUAAUGGUGUCUUUUUCUUGUAGUUUUUUUAAUGCAGGUGGAAUUAUCAGUCUUUCAUUUUUUUCUUCUGUGUUCUACCUGUUUCACAGGUAGAAAAGCCUUAGCUCUUUGAGAUUAUGUUUAAAUGCCCUGUAUUUUCAUCUAGUGGUUUUAUGGUUUUAUUUUGUAUGUUUUUUUCAUCCACCUGGAAUUUAUUUUGCUGUUAAAAUAUGAAUUAGAGAUCCAACUUAAUUUUUUUCAGAUGGUUGUUGACUUAUUGCAAUAUCAUGUGUUAUAUAAUCCAUCUUUACUGAUUCGUUGCUAAUUGGUUUCUGGACUUUUAAGGCUAUCUGAUGAACUGUUGAUCUGGUACCACACUGUUUCAAUUAUUGUAGUCUUAAAAUUGCUGUACGCUUUGGUAGGGAUAAUUUUCUGUUAAGUGUUUUUGUUUUUUAUAAUUUUCCAAUUAGUCUUGCUCAUUUUUUAUAUAAACUUUGAAAUCAAUUUUUCUGAUUUUCAAAAGAAAAAAAAUCCUGUUUAGUAUUCUUAGUGGAAUGAAUUAAAUUUCCAUAGCAAUUUAGGGAAAUUUGACUUUCUUAACGUGUUGAGUGUUAAACCCACAGGUGGUAGCAUGACAUUGACUCCUCAGCCAAGCAUAUUAUCAACUGUCGGAAACUAGGUUUUCCCAUAGUGAUCCAAGAAACUAGUACGAAAUGCCUUUCUGAUUUUUUAAAACUUGUAUACAUAUAUAGUACAUAUUAUAUAUACUUAUAUAUUAAGUAAUCAGAAGUAUGUGUUUCUCAAUCACCUUUUAAAGACUUCUUUAUAUAGCUCUUGUACAUUUCUUGAUAUGAAUAUGUUAAUGUUUUCUUUCAUUAUGUUGCAUAUGGCUUUUGUUUUCUGCAUGAAAACUAUUGAUUUCUGCAUUCUAAUUUUGUUCCCAGUCACCUAACUGAAUUCUUCUAACAGUUGUAAUAAAUUUCUGGUUGGCUCUCUUGUGUUUUCUAGGUAAACAA